UGUGGGAUGAUGGGGAGGGUUCCCACAAAGAUGGAGCCUCGUCAGCCUUUCUCCAGCACCGGAAACCACAGGAAACCAGGCCAUGCAGCCAUGUUCCGGGAGCCCUAAUUGCACAGAAGCCCAUGGGGAGCUCCAGACUGGCAGCCCUGCUCCUGCCUCUCCUCCUCAUAGUCAUCGACCUCUCUGACUCUGCUGGGAUUGGCUUUCGCCACCUGCCCCACUGGAACACCCGCUGUCCUCUGGCCUCCCACACGGAUGACAGUUUCACUGGAAGUUCUGCCUAUAUCCCUUGCCGCACCUGGUGGGCCCUCUUCUCCACAAAGCCUUGGUGUGUGCGAGUCUGGCACUGUUCCCGCUGUUUGUGCCAGCAUCUGCUGUCAGGUGGCUCAGGUCUUCAACGGGGCCUCUUCCACCUCCUGGUGCAGAAAUCCAAAAAGUCUUCCACAUUCAAGUUCUAUAGGAGACACAAGAUGCCAGCACCUGCUCAGAGGAAGCUGCUGCCUCGUCGUCACCUGUCUGAGAAGAGCCAUCACAUUUCCAUCCCCUCCCCAGACAUCUCCCACAAGGGACUUCGCUCUAAAAGGACCCAACCUUCGGAUCCAGAGACAUGGGAAAGUCUUCCCAGAUUGGACUCACAAAGGCAUGGAGGACCCGAGUUCUCCUUUGAUUUGCUGCCUGAGGCCCGGGCUAUUCGGGUGACCAUAUCUUCAGGCCCUGAGGUCAGCGUGCGUCUUUGUCACCAGUGGGCACUGGAGUGUGAAGAGCUGAGCAGUCCCUAUGAUGUCCAGAAAAUUGUGUCUGGGGGCCACACUGUAGAGCUGCCUUAUGAAUUCCUUCUGCCCUGUCUGUGCAUAGAGGCAUCCUACCUGCAAGAGGACACUGUGAGGCGCAAAAAAUGUCCCUUCCAGAGCUGGCCAGAAGCCUAUGGCUCGGACUUCUGGAAGUCAGUGCACUUCACUGACUACAGCCAGCACACUCAGAUGGUCAUGGCCCUGACACUCCGCUGCCCACUGAAGCUGGAAGCUGCCCUCUGCCAGAGGCACGACUGGCAUACCCUUUGCAAAGACCUCCCGAAUGCCACAGCUCGAGAGUCAGAUGGGUGGUAUGUUUUGGAGAAGGUGGACCUGCACCCCCAGCUCUGCUUCAAGUUCUCUUUUGGAAACAGCAGCCAUGUUGAAUGCCCCCACCAGACUGGGUCUCUCACAUCCUGGAAUGUAAGCAUGGAUACCCAAGCCCAGCAGCUGAUUCUUCACUUCUCCUCAAGAAUGCAUGCCACCUUCAGUGCUGCCUGGAGCCUCCCAGGCUUGGGGCAGGACACUUUGGUGCCCCCCGUGUACACUGUCAGCCAGGCCCGGGGCUCAAGCCCAGUGUCACUAGACCUCAUCAUUCCCUUCCUGAGGCCAGGGUGCUGUGUCCUGGCUAGCAGCUGGAGCAGACACAAACCCACCUGGGAAGAAUUCCCUAGCCAGUGGGGACUCCCCUCUCCCCCAGCUCCAUGCUUCACUCAGCUCCCCGGGAGGAGAAGAUGCCUGGCUCAUAGGGGUGGGGGGCUCUGUGCCCUCAGGUGUGGCGGUCAGAUGUCCAGUUUGCCUGGAAGCACCUCUUGUGUCCGGAUGUCUCUUACAGACACCUGGGGCUCUUGAUCCUGGCACUGCUGGCCCUCCUCACCCUACUGGGUGUUGUUCUGGCCCUCACCUGCCGGCGCCCACAGUCAGGUAAGCUCACCUGGGGUAACCUGGGAAGUCAGACCUGCCCAGCUCGGAGACUAGCUGCCCCCUCACCCUCCCCUGUCUGAGCUCUCAGCACUGCACCCAAUCUCUGUUACCCAGGCAGGGAGCCUCAGGCCCCCAAGUGAGCAGGAAUGGUUAAGGCAAGGCAAAGGGCCCUCUGAGCAUAUUGUCACUGUACUGAGUCUCUGUACAAAAGGCUAGUGGGGCAGAAAUCCAGCCUGCGCUGUACUCGCCCAGCCUGGAGCCCUGACCCUCUCUUCAGAAGGGGUGCCUUUAUCUAAUUAGCCCAUAAGCACCCUAUAGGCUAGGGCUGUUUUCGGUACCAACCCCCAGAGCAAAUAAGGGGCGGGGGCGGGGGCGGAGAGGCGAGCACCCUACGGUAUCCCGAGAGGGUGGGGAGAAGAGGGCUGAGCAGUCCCUCAGCCGCCCAGCCUUCAUCUGUUGCUUCCCGCCACCAGGCCCGGGCCCAGCGCGGCCAGUGCUCCUCCUGCACGCGGCGGACUCGGAGGCGCAGCGGCGCCUGGUGGGAGCGCUGGCUGAACUGCUACGGGCAGCGCUGGGCGGCGGGCGCGACGUGAUCGUGGACCUGUGGGAGGGGAGGCACGUGGCGCGCGUGGGCCCGCUGCCGUGGCUCUGGGCGGCGCGGACGCGCGUAGCGCGGGAGCAGGGCACUGUGCUGCUGCUGUGGAGCGGCGCCGACCUUCGCCCGGUCAGCGGCCCCGACCCCCGCGCCGCGCCCCUGCUCGCCCUGCUCCACGCUGCCCCGCGCCCGCUGCUGCUGCUCGCUUACUUCAGUCGCCUCUGCGCCAAGGGCGACAUCCCCCCGCCGCUGCGCGCCCUGCCGCGCUACCGCCUGCUGCGCGACCUGCCGCGUCUGCUGCGGGCGCUGGACGCGCGGCCUUUCGCAGAGGCCACCAGCUGGGGCCGCCUUGGGGCGCGGCAGCGCAGGCAGAGCCGCCUAGAGCUGUGCAGCCGGCUCGAACGAGAGGCCGCCCGACUUGCAGACCUAGGUUGAGCAGAGCUCCACCGCAGUCCCGGGUGUCUGCGGCCGCAACGCAACGGACACUGGCUGGAACCCCGGAAUGAGCCUUCGACCCUGAAAUCCUUGGGGUGCCUCGAGGACGACUGGCCGAAAAGCCGCAUUCCCUGCCUCACAGGCCGGAAGUCCCAGCCCAGUCCCCGCGCGCGUCCCUCUUCCUCCUCAUACUUUCCCUUGACUGAGAGCUCCUCUAACCCCUGUUCUGAUGGGGGAGGGCGGUCUUCCCACUUCCUCUCCAGAACUCCAGAAAGAGCAGUGUGCUUAUGCUUCAGUCCAGGCUGGAGAGGUUGGGGCCGGGGUAGGGAGGCAGGAGCCAUGUCAGUUCUGAAGGAGGGUGAGGCGGUGGGGGAUUGCAGGGGGCGGCUGAGAGAAAACCUCCUUGGGGGCCAGGGAUUCCCUUUCCCACUCUGAGGCUCUGGCCAGAGGGAGAGAGGACUCUGGACCUAGGAAAAGAGGCUUUUGGCUCCAGGUGGUCAGGACAGUGGGGGUUGGGGGUGGGGUGGGUGGGUGCUGGCGGUGGGGACCAAGAUCCGGAAAGAUGAAUAAAGACAAACAUGACAAACUAA